GCAGCAGGGGUGGUCGCCAUGGAGACGCGUGGCCCUGGCCUGGCGGUCCGCGCUGAGAGUCGCCGAUUAGUCGGCAUCGGGCCUCGGGCGCCCCCGGGGCGGGUUGGGUUGCAGCCCAGCGGGCGGCUGGACCGCCGCGGUGGGGCGGGGACAAUGGGGUACAAGGACAACGACGGCGAGGAGGAGGAGCGGGAGGGCGGCGCCGCGGGCCCGCGGGGGUCUAGACUGCCCCCCAUCACAGGCGGCGCCUCCGAGCUGGCCAAACGGAAGGUGAAGAAGAAAAAAAGGAAGAAGAAGACCAAGGGGUCUGGCAAGGGGGACGAUAAACAUCAGAGUCAGAGCCUGAAGAGCCAGCCGCUUUCUUCCUCCUUUCAUGACAUCUUAAGUCCUUGCAAAGAGCGUGGCCCGAAACCAGAGCACAGACAGAGCAAAGUGGAAAAGAAGCACCUCCCUUCUGACUCCUCCACCGUCAGCCUCCCCGACUUUGCCGAAAUAGAGAACCUUGCGAAUCGGAUCAACGAAAGUCUGCGUUGGGAUGGAAUUCUUGCUGACCCGGAGGCAGAGAAGGAAAGGAUUCGCAUCUAUAAACUGAAUCGGAGAAAACGGUACCGGUGCUUGGCCCUCAAGGGCUUCCACCCCGACCCCGAGGCCCUCAAGGGCUUCCACCCCGACCCCGACGCCCUCAAGGGCUUCCACCCCGACCCCGAGGCCCUCAAGGGCUUCCACCCCGACCCCGAGGCCCUCAAGGGCAUCCACCCCGACCCCGAGGCUCUCAAGGGCUUCCACCCCGACCCCGAGGCCCUCAAGGGCUUCCACCCCGACCCUGAGGCCCUCAAGGGUUUCCACACUGACCCCGAGGCCCUCAAGGGUUUCCACAUUGACCCCGAGGCCCUCAAGGGCUUCCACCCCGACCCCAAGGCCCUCAAGGGCUUCCACCCCGACCCCAAGGCCCUCAAGGGUUUCCACACUGACCCCGAGGCCCUCAAGGGCUUCCACCCCGACCCCAAGGCCCUCAAGGGCUUCCACCCCGACCCCGAGGCCCUCAAGGGCUUCCACCCCGACCCCGAGGCCCUCAAGGGCUUCCACCCCGACCCCGAGGCCCUCAAGGGCUUCCACACUGACCCCAAUGCCGAGGAGGCCCCUGAGAACUUACCCUACCUCUCGGACAAAGAUGGCAGCUCCAGCCACAGGCAGCCCACGUCGAAAGCCGAGUGCCCCAAUCUCUGUUUUGAAGGAAACCUUACCCCAAAGCUUCUACACUCUGACUUAGCUCCUACUCUGCUGGAGUGAAAAUCUACCCACGACGCUCACAAACUUAUAAUUCCUCCUCACCACAAGUUUAUGUGUUAAAAACCAUCAUCAUAAAAGGAAAUGAGACCCGUAUCUGAAGGAAACAGAUGUUCGGUACACGGACGACGCCGACUCUCCCAUCACCAAGCUGCCCUCGGUUGCCCAGGAGAGCCACAGUGCCUUGAGAACAUAAGCAAUUUAGUGAACAGAGUUCUUUUCAGAAUUUCCUUUUUCUUAAGUAAGCAUCUCUGUUACUUAAUUUCUCACCACAGCUAGAUGUCUAUAAUCUGCCCCAAAAAGAAAAGAAAGCGUGUAGAUGAUUUACCUCUUAAGUCUCAAUCUCAUGGUGAAACUCCUCACACGGUACCUGCUUCUGUUGGCCGGAGGACGAUGCCCUGAACCUCUUGGAGCCUUUUUCUGUUUUAAUUAAAUGCAUGGCCUGCCUUUAUAUGGCCUCAAAUAAGUGGGUUCCAGAACUCCAUCCCUGGGAAGUUACCAUGGGAAGUCCCAAGAGGAAUACUGCUUCUUUCAUAAACAUGGUCCUCUCCUAA